GGGAGCUGCCAGGAGCUCUGGGAUUCCAGCGGCUGGAAGACCGUGAAUUCUCUGCCGGGUCAGAGCCGCGGAGCCAGUGUGGAAACAGCCCAGGACGGUUAUGAAAUGAGCCCGGGGGCCACGACUUGCUUGGCCGGUUGGACGUCCUCACCCUGCCGCCGGGGCCUGCGUGGGGACGGCCACCUGGGAAGCCUGGCCUCAGUGUGGAAGAGAAGGCAGCAGGAUUAUUACAGAACCUUGUGAAGCCAACGCGGGCAGCCGCCAGGAGCUGCAGACCGAGAGGAUCUCGUCCUUUCUUGCGGCCCAGGGAGACCAGGCCUUUCAUUCUGGGCUCGAGACCAACAAUUCGAAUUCCGAACUCCCCCUGCGUGUGGGACUCAAGGUUGCCCAGGGCUCACCUCUGAUGGGUGGGCAGGUGAGCGCUUCCAACAGCUUCUCGAGGCUGCACUGCAGAAAUGCCAACGAGGACUGGAUGUCGGCACUGUGUCCCCGGCUCUGGGAUGUGCCCCUCCACCACCUCUCCAUCCCAGGGAGCCACGACACGAUGACGUACUGCCUGAACAAGAAGUCCCCCAUUUCGCACGAGGAGUCCCGGCUGCUGCAGCUGCUGAACAAGGCCUUGCCCUGCAUCACGCGCCCUGUCGUGCUGAAAUGGUCCGUCACCCAGGCACUGGACGUCACAGAGCAGCUGGAUGCCGGGGUGCGGUACCUGGACCUGCGGAUAGCCCACAUGCUGGAGGGCUCGGAGAAGAACCUGCACUUUGUCCAUAUGGUGUACACAACGGCGCUGGUGGAGGACACACUCACGGAAAUCUCGGAGUGGCUGGAGCGGCAUCCACGCGAGGUGGUCAUCCUGGCCUGCAGAAACUUCGAGGGGCUGAGCGAGGACCUGCACGAGUACCUGGUCGCCUGUAUCAAGAACAUCUUCGGGGACAUGCUGUGUCCUCGUGGGGAGGUGCCGACACUGCGGCAGCUGUGGUCCCGGGGCCAACAGGUCAUCGUCUCCUAUGAAGACGAGAGCUCCUUGCGCCGGCACCACGAGCUGUGGCCAGGAGUCCCCUACUGGUGGGGAAACAGGGUGAAGACCGAGGCCCUCAUCCGAUACCUGGAGACCAUGAAGAGCUGCGGCCGCCCAGGAGGGUUGUUCGUGGCCGGCAUCAACCUCACGGAGAACCUGCAGUACGUUCUGGCGCACCCGUCCGAGUCCCUGGAGAAGAUGACGCUGCCCAACCUUCCGCGGCUGAGCGCGUGGGUCCGAGAGCAGUGCCCGGGGCCGGGUUCACGGUGCACCAACAUCAUCGCGGGGGACUUCAUCGGCGCAGACGGCUUCGUCAGUGACGUCAUCGCGCUCAAUCAGAAGCUGCUGUGGUGCUGACGGGACCCUUCUGAAGUUCGGGACGCGGCGGCUGCAGUUUCACCCCCGAAUUUCCAAGUAUUGUGACUUUGUUUGGGCCAAAUGUUGGUGAUCAUAGGACCGAUGAUAAUACGUUUUCAUUUUCUUUAAAAUAGAGAUGGGGUGGCUGGGCGUGGUGACUUCGCCUGUCUUCCCAGCACUUUGGGAGGCCGAGGUGGGUGGAUCAUGAGGUCAGGAGCUUGAGAGCAGCCUGACCAACAUGGUGAAAUCCCAUCUCUACUAAAAAUACAAAACUUAGCUGGGUGUGUGGCAGGCGCCUGUAGUCCCAGUUACUCGGGAGGCUCAGGCAGGAGAACUGCUUGAAGCCGGGAGAUGGAGGUUGCAUUGAGCUGACAUCGUGCCACUGCACUCCAGUCUGAAUGAUAGACCGAGACUCCAUCUCAAAAGAAAAAAAAACAGCCGAGUGUGCAGUGACUCACGCCUGUCAUCCCAGCACUUUGGGAGGCGAAGGCGGGUGGAACAUGAGGUCAGGAGUUCGAGACCAGCCUGACCAACAUGGUGAAACCCCGUCUCUAUUAAAAACACAAAAACUACCUGGGUGCGUGAUGGGCACCUGUAGUGCCAGCUACUCAGGAGGCUGAGGCAGGAGAAUGGCGUGAACCCGGGAGGUGGAGGUUGCAUUGAGCUGAGAUCGUGCCACUGCACUCCAGCCUGGGCGACAGAGCGAGACUCCAUCUCAAAAAAAAAAAAAAAAAAAAAGAUGGGGUCUCUCUAUGUUGGCCAGGUUGGUCUUGAACUCCUGGCCUCAAGUGAUCCUCCCACCUCAGCCUCCCAGAGUGCUGGGAUGACAGUCAAGAACCACCAUGGCAGCCCAUAAUAUGUUUUCUUAUUUCUGUAUUCUCCUUGCUGUGGCGUCUGGAGCCCUUACAGACCCAGGGAGACACUAUCCUCCCACAGCUCACUAAUUACUAAACACAGUGACAGCCCACUUAGGAGCCGGCCUCCCCUGUCAGCCAACCCCUCAGCUAGUUCUCACACCAAGCCUAUAGAUAUAUAUGUGUGUGUAUAUAUGUGUGUUUAUGUGUCUGUGUGUAUAUAUGUGUAUAUAUCGGUGUGUAUAUAUGUAUGUAUGUUUAUACAUGUGUAUAUGUGUGUGUGUGUGUGUAUAUGUGUGUAUGUGUGUAUAUAUGUAUAUGUGUGCAUAUGUGUAUACGUGUAUGCAUACAUGUAUAUGUGUAUGCAUGUAUAUGUGUAUGUGUACAUGUAUAUGUGUUUAUACAUGUAUAUGUGUGUAUGCGUGUAUACGUGUAUGUAUACAUGUAUAUGUGUGUAUGCGUGUAUAUACACACGUAUACAUAUAUACGUGCGUGUGUAUGUGUAUAUAUAUAUAUGUGUAUAUAUAUAUUUUUUGAGGAGUCUCACUCUGUCACCCAGGCUGGAGUGCAACGGCGAGAUCUCGGCUCACCGCAACCUCCGCCUCCCUGGUUCAAGCAAUUCUCCUGCCUCCGCCUCCCGAGUAGCUGGGAUGACAGGCAUGUGCCACCACACCCGACUAAUUUCAUAUAUUUAGUAGAGACGGGGUUUCUCCGCGUUGGUCAGGCCGUUCUCAAACUUCUGACCUCAGGUGAUCUGCCCGCCUCGACCUCCCAAAGUGCUGGGAUGACAGGCAUGAGCCACUGUGCCCAGCCGCCGAUAUUUCUUUAAAUUAUGUUUAGGGACAGGGUCUUUUUCUGUCACCCAGGCUGGAGGGCAGUGGUACAGUCAUAGCUCACUGCAGCCUCAACCUCCUGGGCUCAAGCGAUCCUCUCAGCUCAGCCUCCCGUGUAGCUGGGGCUCCAGGGACACACCCCCACUGCUGGCUAAUUUUUGUAUUUUUGGUAGAGUCAGGGUUUCACCACAUGGCACAGUCUGGUCUCAAAUUCCUGGGCUCCAGUGAUCCUCCCACCUUAGCUUCCAGAGUGGCCAGGAUCACAGGCAGGCACCACCAUGCCCAGGUAAUUUUAUUUUUUUGUAGAGACGUGGUCUGGCUAUGUUGUCCAGGGUGGUCUCAAACUCCUGGGCUCAACUGAUCCUCCCACCUCAACCUCUGCCAUAGCCAGGACCUCAGGUGUCAGCCACCACACCCACAGCUAAUUUUUUUUGUAGAGAUGGGGUCUGGCUCUGUUGCUCAGGCUGGUGUGUAGUAGGGGCACAGUCAUAGCUCACUGUAACCUUCAACGCCUGGGCUGAAGCAAUUCUCCCGCCUCAGCUUCCCAAGUAACUGGGAGUAUAGGUGUACACCACCAUGCCCAGCUAAUUAUUUAGUAGUAGUAGGAGGAGUAUUAUGUUUGAGAUGGAGUCUCGCUCUGUCGCCCAGGCUGGAGUGCAGUGGCGCAGUCUCAGCUCACUGCAACCUCUGCCUCCCAGGUUCAAGCAAUUCUUGUGCCUCAGCCUCCUGAGUAGCUGGGAUUACAGGCGCCCGCCACCGCGCCUGGCUAACUUUUGUAUUUUUAGCAGAGAUGGGGUUUCACCAUGUUGCCCAGGCUGGUCUUGAACUCCCGACCUCAGGUGAUCCAUCCGCAUUGGCCUCCCAAAGUGCUGGGAUCACAGGCGUGAGCCACCGCACCUGGCCUCAAGCCAGUAUUUCCCUGGCCCUAAAUCAUUCCUGGCUGGGUCCCAGCCCAGUAGAGCCAGCCCCCCAGCCCGGAGUGCUACUGAAGUGUUCAAAAGUUGUCAAUCCUCAGCCGUUCCCUAGUCCUGUUGCCCGGUUCUGCCGAAGCCCCUUGAAGGCUGUGGCCUGGGCUGUUCCCUCAUUCAUUCCUGCCUCCCGAGCCAAACCCAGGUAUCCGCUUGUGCCCUGCGUGGUGUGGCAGCGUCUUCUCUCGGGAAGGGUCAGGAGUAAUUUCUUCUUUCAGUGGCCUCUCUGUGCUAGUCCCGGUCACCUCCGUGAAUUAAAGUCCUACAGGUACAAGGGAGACCCCCCCCCCACGGAAGGCGCCCCCAGUCCGUGUGGGAGACUCGCACACCGGUUUUCUGCACAGGUUUCUUUCUGCCUCUGAAGCGUGAACGGUCCUAGUUUCAGACGCAGAUCCUGCAAAUACUUUUUUUUGUUUUUUUGAGAUGGAUUUUCCCUCUUGUUGUUCAGGCUGGAGUGCAAUGGCACGAUCUCAGCUCACUGCAACCUCUGCCUCCCGGGUUCAAGUGAUUCUCCUGCCUCAGCCUCCCGAGGAGCUGAGAUUACAGGCGCGUGCCACCGUGCCUGGUUAAUUUUGUAUUUGUAUUUUUAUUUAUGUUUUGAGACGGAGUUUCGCUCUCGUUGCCGAGGCUGGAGUGUAGUAGUGUGAUCCUGGCUCACUGCAACCUCCACCUCCCGGGUUCCAGCAAAUUCUCCUGCCUCAGCCUCCCAAGUAGCUGGGAUUGCAGGCGCCCGCCACCACGCCCGGAUAAUUUUUGUGUGUUUAGCAGAGACGGGGUUUCACCAUGUUGGCCAGGCUGGUCUCGAUCUCCUGACCUCAGGUGAUCCACCCGCCUCGGCCUCCCAAAGUGCUGGGAUGACAGGCGUGAGCCACCGCGCCCGGCCUAUACCUCAUUUUCUACAUGUCGCUUGUUGGAGCUGCUGGUUCAAGUUCCCAGCCAGCCAAUGGAUGCCAGCACCAUUUUUACUCCCCUUUCCCAAGCAAAUCGUGCAUUUUUGUCUAACGAGAGACAUCAGUUUCUCAGGAUGAUCCUCAAGAACGUUAUGGAGUCCAUGUUGCAAUAGGUUCUCUUUGGGACCUAAUGACUCAUUUUCCAAAAAUCCGCUUCUACUUUUGGUACCCGGUUGCUACGGUGAAAUGAAGGUGCCCCGCAUCCAGAAAGACGCACUCCUGGACCACAACCGGCGGCUACCUCAGCCCCACGGCUCUGCAGGAUCAGGGCUCGGGCAGGCCCCGCGGAGAUGAAGAAUUUGCAGGGAGCCUCCCUGACUUCCGUCGGCUGUGAAUCCUUGUCUGUCAGGGGCGUAUCCACAAAAUCACCGAAUUCAUACAGAUCGUUUAAAUAAAUGAACAUCAUUAAAGUCAAA